CCUGCCCUCCUGGAUGUGGCCUAGGCCCAGAAACAGCCUCUGAGGGCAGAAACCGGGGUCUCCCUUCGCCUGGAAAACAAAAGGUUACUCGGCUGCCUGGGCCCGGGUCCUGAGAUCGAGGCUAACUCCGUGAGGACAGAAGGUGUCCAGAAAUGCUCUCCCUAAUCCUCAAUCCCUCCCCCACCUCAUUGCUCCCUUUGACUCUGUCUGUCUCUGUCUCCCUGUGUCUCCAUGUCUGCCUCAUGAGCCUGGGUGAUCUCUUGCUGUGACUGCAUCUGACACGUGUCCUGUACCAAGUGACUUUUUAGGUGUCUCCAACGCAAGAUGUCAUUCUGCUGAGCUUUUUCAGGCUCUGUGCCCAGAUUCUGAGGCCUCUGACCAAUUUGGAGGGUAGCGUCCCAGGUCGGCAGGUCUCUGAGCUGUGGAGGGCUUGUGUCUGGGGUGACAGUCCUCUGGGCUGAUCAGGGUUCUCUCCCAGCAUGUGAGGUGUCUGAUCUGCUUUAGGUAUUGUGUCUAGAAUGCAAGGCAUGGGAGCAGUUCUGAUUUCAGGAAGUAGGGUUUGAGCUCUCCCGAGUGUCUGUGUCAAUGAUAGGACACAAUAGCGCCCCUUGGGGCUCCAUAUCCUAGGUUGUGAGAACACUGAGGUUAUUCCAAACUCACGAAAGGUGUCUGAUCCUUUUGGGGUCCUGCGUCCUGAGUGUGUCCUCCCUACCCGGUUAUGAGUCUGCACCGCAGGGGUUGAGGCUGCUGACAUGUUGAGGAGUUGCUGUGUCUCAGGUUGUAAACUCUGUGCUGUGUGGGAAUGGUGUGUCCCACACUCUGAGGUCUCCUAGGUGUUUGUUGCAGGGAACAUUGUGCCCAAGGCCUCUGUGUUCCCUGUCCCGGUCCCCUCAACUGUUUCUGUGUCCGCAUCUCAGGGUGUGCGCACUGUGGUUUUGUGGGCUUCUGGGUCCGGGCUGUGAGGUCCGUGAGGUAAUCCGUUUUCUACAUCACAGGUUCUAAAGUUGCUCACACGCACGUGGGUCUGAAUUUUAGAAUCUGAUGUCUCUGAGCAGGUUUAGUGUCUGUGUCCUCCUUCACUGAGUUCUUGGAGGGGUCUGAGUUCUGCGAACUGUUCAGUGUUGUGUGUCCAGGGUUGAGGUCUCUGAGCUGCUUGUUCCUGGGUUGUUGUCUGGGUUUUCUAUGUCACUGGGGUCUCUUGGGCUUUGUGACCCAGCCUGUGAGGUCCCUGAGGUAUCUGAGAGUGUGUGUGUCCAGGAUAGGACGUUUCAGAGCUGGUAGGAGAUGUAUGUUUUGGAGGGAGGCCUGUUCUGUCUUUGGUUCCGUGUUCCAGGGAUUGAAACGUCUGAGCUCUUUGGGAGAUCAUCUCAAGCAUGAGAGACACUGUCACAUAGCAAAGUUCAGACAUGAGUUGUUUGUGACCUUCUCCUGAUAUUUGGGUCUCACCCUGUACAGUCAGUGAGAGGUUGUCUUGAGUUGACUUUCCCAGACUCGUCCACUCCAGCCUGCCACAGCCACGCUUACUUAUCUAGACCCCUGAGUUUACACGGCCAGCUUCCUUCACAGCUGCCCCUGGGGUUGGAGUCAUGCGACUGCUUUGAGAGUCACAGGUCCCCCUCAGCACCACUUGUGGAGAUCUCACUGUGCGGAGGAGUUUCUUCUGUGUCUCUGAUAAAAGACACAGAGCAGGGACCCUCUCUCUCAGCGAUGAACAGGACCUGCCCAUGUGUUCCUGGGUCGUGUGGUCUGUCUCCUGCAAGAUGUCACUGACACCCAGAAAAUAACCUGGACACAACAUCCCUCUUGCAGCUCUCCCAGAACACAUGCAUCAAACCCGGGAUCCCCUGUGCCCUGGUGGGAUGGCAGGAGUCUCUAGCUGUUUGGAUCAUCUUCCCAAACCUUAACUUCACCUUUACAUGAUGAGGAUCUACAGAGCGGCAUCUCAGCCCUUUCCUGCAAACGCACGGUGCUUCUGAAUGCAGAAUUCGGGGCUAGGGAAGGGAGGGGACACAGGUAGAUGCCAUCUGUGGUCAGGGGGAGGUGUGGGCCCGAGACCGUCUCAGCUGAAAUGUAGGAGUAAUGGGCACAGACCAUUCAAGAGAAAUGUGUGUUGGGCUGAAGAAAGUAGAAACUACCUCCAGAGUAUCUCCUCCAUCUCUAAGACAUGCACGGUUUAAUUCUGUUAUUUUGUGAGGCUCUUUGCACCAUGACACAAGCAUGCAUAGAGGGCUCCAUCAUACAGGGGAGAACGAGACCCUGAAUGGUCUCACAGUCUAGUGGGGGAGGCAUAUGUGUUCCUUCAGGCAACAAAUAUGUAUGAAAGUCUUCUACGUGCCAGGCACUGCUUGAGGUGUAGGGAUACCUCAGGGAAGCAAAUCAACAGAAAUCCCUGCCCUGGAUCUGACAUUCCCCGAAGAGGACGUGGUAGGUGGCAGACAGCAAACCCUCCACAAGGGAAUCUAGGAAACGUUAGAAGUUAUGAACCAAAACGUACCCGAGACAGGUCUCAAUCAAUUUAGAAGUUUAUUUUGCCAAGGUUAAGGACGUGCCCCUGACACAACCUCAGGAGGUCCUGACGAAACAUCCCCAAGGUCGUCAGGGUACAGCUUCGCUUUAUACACUUUAGGGAGACAUAAGACAUCAAUCAAUGCAUGUACGACAUACAUUGAUUCCUUCUGAAAAGGCGGGACAACUACAAGUUGGCGGGCGGUGGAGGGGCGGUGGGGUCUUACAGGUCAUAAGUGGAUUCAAAGAUUUUCUGAUUGGCAAUUGCUUGAGUUUAUCUAAAGACCUCCAAUCCAUAGGAGGGAGUGUCUGGGUUAAGAUAAGGGGUUGUGGAGAUCAAGGUUCUUAUUAUGCCAAUGAAGUCCCGAGGCAGCCGGCUUCAGAGAGAAUAGACUGUAAAUAUUUCUUAUCAGACCUUAAAAGUUGCUGGACUCUUGGGAACUAAUUCUCUCCUAGACCAGGAAAAAGACCUGGAAAGGGAAAGGGAUUCUCUACAGAAUGUAGACUUCCUCACAAGAGAUGGCUUUGUAGGCCUAUUUCAAAAUGUGUCAAAGAAAUGUAUUGUUGGAUGAAACACUUUGACUUCUUUCAGGGCCUAUUUGUUAUGUGAUGCUAUACUAGUCAGGCUGGAACUUGGUGUCUUAUUGCCACAGUCUUAAGAUCUCUCCCUUAACAUAAAUGCUGGUCAGUUGUGCCUGAAUUCCAUAGGGAGAAGGGUGUAAUGACGCAUGUCUGACCCACCCUUCCCAUCAUGGCCUGAACUACUUUUUCAGGCUAACUUUGGAAAAGCUUUGGCCGAGAGGAAGGGUCCAUUCAGAUGGUUGGGGAGUGGGGCUUAGAAUUUUAUUUUUAGUUUACAAAGAUGAUGGGGGCUGUGUUAAAAAGAAAAAAUAUACAGAUCACAGUACAGGGAUUGGGAAUUGGGGGAGGCACUGGGUUAGCUGCAGGUAAAUUAUAACAGAGUGACUAGGGUAGGCUGGGUUGAGAAGGUGACAAUUUGACAAAGAUGUGAAGGGGGAGGAGUCAGUCAAGCAGAUAUCUGUGGUGAAGGCCUUCCAGACAGAGGGAGCAGUUGGAAAAAAGUCAGAGGCUGAGUCGUUCCAACAUGGCGCAGAUGCCACAAGGACACUAGCACACCAGCAGGAAGCUGAACAGAAGGCUGGAGGUGCCACGGUGACAAGGACGGGAUCCUGUCAGGCCAGAUGGACUCACCCUGUCACCCAGGUUGGACUGCACUGGCCUCAACCUCCUGAGUUCAAGUGAUCGUCCCACCUCAGCCUCCCCAGUAGCUGGGACCAUAGCUGUGCAGCAUCAUGCCUGGCUAAUUUUUUAAGUUUUUUGUUGAGAUGGUGGUCUCGCCCUGUUGCUCAGGCUGGCCUCAAACUCCUGGGCUGAAGCAGUCCUCCCACCUCAGCCUCCCAAAGUGCUUGGAUUAGAGGCGUGAGCCACCAUUCCUGGCUCCUUGGACAAUAUUUUAUUCCUCAGAUUAAGACACGUCCUUGGGAUGGGGCUGCAUUGGAUAAUUCACCGAAGGCACCGCUGAAUGGAGUGGGCCCUCAGUAAAUACCUGGAGGAAUGUGACCUGGCCAGUGAGGUUAUUUUCUUUUGUAGGUGAAAGGUGUAGCAGUCACUCGGCCUACACCCACAGCAUCGACCUUGUGAACCCAGCGACCUGACUGCCUUGGGAGAAUUGAAGCGAAUGAGAGUGGGGAGUGUGAGAGGUGCGUUUGGUGCAGCAUUUCUGGCAUGGGAACAGAACUGGCCAGGAGGAAGUGACGUCUGGGUUCUGCCCGCACACAUUCCUCGCCACCUUCUUGGUGUCUGAGAACCUCCAGCUUCACCUCCUUUUCUGGACCCGAGGGCCUGGCGGAGCUUCCAGCUGGGACCAGACCUCCAUGGAUCCACUCCAGAAACGGAAUCCAGCAUCGCCUUCCAAAUCUUCCCCGAUGACAGCUGCAGAGACUUCCCAGGAAGGUCCAGCGCCCUCUCAGCCUUCGUACUCAGAACAGCCGAUGAUGGGCCUCAGUAACCUGAGCCCCGGUCCUGGCCCCAGCCAGGCCGUGCCUCUCCCAGAGGGGCUGCUCCGCCAGCGGUACAGAGAGGAGAAGACCCUGGAAGAGCGGCGGUGGGAGAGGCUGGAGUUCCUUCAGAGGAAGAAAGCAUUCCUGCGGCAUGUGAGGAGGAGACACCGCGAUCACAUGGCCCCCUAUGCUGUUGGGAGGGAAGCCAGAAUCUCCCCAUUAGGUGACAGAAGUCAGAAUCGAUUCCGAUGUGAAUGUCGAUACUGCCAGAGCCACAGGCCGAAUCUUUCUGGGAUCCCUGGGGAGAGUAACAGGGCCCCACAUCCCUCCUCCUGGGAGACGCUGGUGCAGGGCCUCAGUGGCUUGACUCUCAGCCUAGGCACCAACCAGCCCGGGCCUCUGCCUGAAGCGGCACUCCAGCCACAGGAGACAGAGGAGAAGCGCCAGCGAGAGAGGCAGCAGGAGAGCAAAAUAAUGUUUCAGAGGCUGCUCAAGCAGUGGUUAGAGGAAAACUGAGACGUGCACCCCCAUGGGAUGGAGACCCGAAGGGACUCAGACGGAGCCGCCGUGUUGGCAGCGCCUGGGUGUGGGCCCAUUUUGGGGACCAAACAGCAAGCUGUGGUCGGAUGAGUGCCAGGACCUGUGUACCGGGACACGUGGGAGUCCUCCCAGCAUGAUGCUUGACUGACCCGAGGAAGGUCCUCAUGUUUCGUGCCUGUCAUUCUCGGAUGGCUGUGAGGCAUUCCUUGGCAAGGGACGCUGCGUACCAGCGGUCCUCACCGCAUCUCACAUGGCUCCUGUGAUGCAUGUUGUCGCUUUCCCACCCGGGAUCUCCAUCUCUCUUCCCUUCCUGCUGUCAGUAAGAGAUCACAUGUCUGUGUAGUGUGAAUGCCUUGUCGCUGUCCUGUGCUUUUGCACCAUUGAGUUGACUGCCUCUGAGAAGCAGCACUAGGCCUGUUGAAAUGCAAUGUGCUGCCCUGAGAUCCAGUUUCAAGAAUGGGCAGGUAAACGCAGUGUGGGAAAGGAAUGUGGAAUGAGAACUUGGUGGUUCACCGCUGUACUAUUUGUGUAAAUGUUUACGUAUGUGAUAAGCUACAUGUAUGUAAAUGUUGCAAUACCCCUAACAGUCGAGUAGUAGUCUCCCUUACAGGAAUUUUUGACGGGGUUCCUCAUCAUCAAUACCAAAUAAAUAUAUGUAGGAAUGGAAAA